AGUCACACUUCAGAAAUAUCCUCCUACACCUCAACUGAAAUCUAACCUCCUGAAAUCAUGUGUUGCAACUACUACAGAAACUGCUGUGGGGGCUGUGGAUAUGGCUCUGGCUGGAGUUCCGGCUGUGGAUAUGGUUGUGGCUAUGGCUGUGGAUACGGCUCUGGCUGUAGAUAUGGCUCUGGCUAUGGAACUGGCUGUGGCUAUGGCUGUGGAUACGGCUCUGGCUGUGGAUAUGGCUGUGGAUACAGCUCUAGCUGCUGUGGCUACCGACCACUUUGCUACAGAAGAUGCUAUUCCUCUUGCUACUAAUCAUCACUACAGGUCAUCCUUGGCUUUGCAAUGACCUCUCCAAGAUCAAGUUCAAUUGAAAUCUCCCCUACCCAUUAUCUUCACAUCUAAGUAAAGGUUGACUAUGGUCACCUGACUAUCUGAAUGCAUAUAAGAGAAGCUGUUGGCAGUGGAUGGA